AGAGUCCCGCGCCCCGCACUCCAUGGAGCAGCUGCUGCGCGCCGAGCUGCGCACCGCGACCCUGCGGGCCUUCGGCGGCCCCGGCGCCGGCUGCAUCAGCGAGGGCCGAGCCUACGACACGGACGCAGGCCCAGUGUUCGUCAAAGUCAACCGCAGGACGCAGGCCCGGCAGAUGUUUGAGGGGGAGGUGGCCAGCCUGGAGGCCCUCAGGAGCACGGGCCUGGUGCGGGUGCCGAGGCCCAUGAAGGUCAUCGACCUGCCGGGAGGUGGGGCCGCCUUUGUGAUGGAGCAUUUGAAGAUGAAGAGCUUGAGCAGUCAAGCAUCAAAACUUGGAGAGCAGAUGGCAGAUUUGCAUCUUUACAACCAGAAGCUCAGGGAGAAGUUGAAGGAGGAGGAGAACACAGUGGGCCGAAGAGGUGAGGGUGCUGAGCCUCAGUAUGUGGACAAGUUCGGCUUCCACACGGUGACGUGCUGCGGCUUCAUCCCGCAGGUGAAUGAGUGGCAGGAUGACUGGCCGACCUUUUUCGCCCGGCACCGGCUCCAGGCGCAGCUGGACCUCAUUGAGAAGGACUAUGCUGACCGAGAGGCACGAGAACUCUGGUCCCGGCUACAGGUGAAGAUCCCGGAUCUGUUUUGUGGCCUAGAGAUUGUCCCCGCGUUGCUCCACGGGGAUCUCUGGUCGGGAAACGUGGCUGAGGACGACGUGGGGCCCAUUAUUUACGACCCGGCUUCCUUCUAUGGCCAUUCCGAGUUUGAACUGGCAAUCGCCUUGAUGUUUGGGGGGUUCCCCAGAUCCUUCUUCACCGCCUACCACCGGAAGAUCCCCAAGGCUCCGGGCUUCGACCAGCGGCUGCUGCUCUACCAGCUGUUUAACUACCUGAACCACUGGAACCACUUCGGGCGGGAGUACAGGAGCCCUUCCUUGGGCACCAUGCGAAGGCUGCUCAAGUAGCGGCCCCUGCCCUCCCUUCCCCUGUCCCCGUCCCCGUCUCCGUCUCCCCGUCCCUGUCCCCCCGUCCCCCGUCCCUGUGCCCCCGUCCCUGUCCCCCUGUUCCCGUCUCCCCGUCCCUCCGUCUCCAUCCCCCCGUCCCCCCAUCCUCCUGUCCCCGUCCCCCCGUCCCCGUCCCUCCAUCCCUGUCCCCCGUCCCCCUGUCCCCCUGUCCACAUACCAAUCCCCCUGUCCCCGACCCCCCAUCCCCGUCCCCCAUCUCCGUCCCCGUCCCCCCUGCCCCGUCCCCGUCUCCGUUCCCCCGUCCCCAUCCUCCAUCCCCGUCUCCCAUCGCCGUCCCCCCGUCCCCGUCCCCCGUCCCCGUCCCCCCUGUCCCUGUCCCCCUUCCCCCGACCCCUCCCAGAUCCUGGGGACCAAUAAAGCCCGCAGCGGGUCUCGGCUGGC